AGGGGAUUGAAGGCUGGGCAGAGUCUGAGUCCACCCGGGUCGUGCUCCCCCCGCUCGCCCGGCUCCUCCGCAGUCCAGGAAUCUCCCCGUGGCUCUCCCCGACCUGGAGGGGUGGACGCCCCUGGCCCCCAGUCCCCGGCCUGCGGAGGGGGCCGGUGGCUGCGGCCCUGCGCGGGGCCGGGGCGGGCCGAGCCAAGGGCCGCCCCCGGCCGACCCUCCCCCUGCCGGGCCCGCCCUCCCCGCCGCGGCGCUGGAGGAGGGCGGGGCGGGGCCCUGGGGUCAGUCUGAGCCUCCGGCACCGGCCGCGCAGCUGGAGGCGGCGGAGCGGAAGCCCCACCAUGGCUGCAAUCCGAAAGAAGCUGGUGAUCGUUGGGGAUGGUGCCUGUGGGAAGACCUGCCUCCUCAUCGUCUUCAGCAAGGAUCAGUUUCCGGAGGUCUACGUCCCUACUGUCUUUGAGAACUAUAUUGCGGACAUUGAGGUGGACGGCAAGCAGGUGGAGCUGGCUCUGUGGGACACAGCAGGGCAGGAAGACUAUGAUCGACUGCGGCCUCUCUCCUACCCGGACACUGAUGUCAUCCUCAUGUGCUUCUCCAUCGACAGCCCUGACAGCCUGGAAAACAUUCCUGAGAAGUGGACCCCAGAGGUGAAGCACUUCUGCCCCAACGUGCCCAUCAUCCUGGUGGGGAAUAAGAAGGACCUGAGGCAAGACGAGCACACCAGGAGAGAGCUGGCCAAGAUGAAGCAGGAGCCCGUUCGGUCUGAGGAAGGCCGGGACAUGGCGAACCGGAUCAGUGCCUUUGGCUACCUUGAGUGCUCAGCCAAGACCAAGGAGGGAGUGCGGGAGGUGUUUGAGAUGGCCACUCGGGCUGGCCUCCAGGUCCGCAAGAACAAGCGUCGGAGGGGCUGUCCCAUUCUCUGAGAUCCCCAAGGCCUUUCCUACAUGCCCCCUCCCUUCACAGGGGUACAGAAAUUAUCCCCCUACAACCCCAGCCUCCUGAGGGCUCCAUGCUGAAGGCUCCCAUUUUCAGUUCCCUCCUGCCCAGGACUGCAUUGUUUUCUAGCCCCGAGGUGGUGGCACGGGCCCUCCCUCCCAGCGCUCUGGGAGCCACGCCUAUGCCCUGCCCUUCCUCAGGGCCCCUGGGGAUCUUGCCCCCUUUGACCUUCCCCAAAGGAUGGUCACACACCAGCACUUUAUACACUUCUGGCUCACAGGAAAGUGUCUGCAGUAGGGGACCCAGAGUCCCAGGCCCCUGGAGUUGUUUUCGGCAGGGGCCUUGUCUCUCACUGCAUUUGGUCAGGGGGGCAUGAAUAAAGGCUACAGGCUCCAA